GCUGAGGGCUGAGGGACGGCUCAGCGACGCCACGGCCAGCAGCGCUCGCGUCCUCCCCAGCAACAGUUACUCAAAGCUAAUCAGAUAGCGAAAGAAGCAGGAGAGCAAGUCAAGAAAUACGGUGAAGGAGUCCUUCCCAAAGUUGUCUAGGUCCUUCCGCGCCGGUGCCUGGUCUUCGUCGUCAACACCAUGGACAGCUCCCGGGAACCGACUCUGGGGCGCUUGGACGCCGCUGGCUUCUGGCAGGUCUGGCAGCGCUUUGAUGCGGAUGAAAAAGGUUACAUAGAAGAGAAGGAACUCGAUGCUUUCUUUCUCCACAUGUUGAUGAAACUGGGUACUGAUGACACGGUCAUGAAAGCAAAUUUGCACAAGGUGAAACAGCAGUUUAUGACUACCCAAGAUGCCUCUAAAGAUGGUCGCAUUCGGAUGAAAGAGCUUGCUGGUAUGUUCUUAUCUGAGGAUGAAAACUUUCUUCUGCUCUUUCGCCGGGAAAACCCACUGGACAGCAGCGUGGAGUUUAUGCAGAUUUGGCGCAAAUAUGACGCUGACAGCAGUGGCUUUAUAUCAGCUGCUGAGCUCCGCAACUUCCUCCGAGACCUCUUUCUUCACCACAAAAAGGCCAUUUCUGAGGCUAAACUGGAAGAAUACACUGGCACCAUGAUGAAGAUUUUUGACAGAAAUAAAGAUGGUCGGUUGGAUCUAAAUGACUUAGCAAGGAUUCUGGCUCUUCAGGAAAACUUCCUUCUCCAAUUUAAAAUGGAUGCUUGUUCUACUGAAGAAAGGAAAAGGGACUUUGAGAAAAUCUUUGCCUACUAUGAUGUUAGUAAAACAGGAGCCCUGGAAGGCCCAGAAGUGGAUGGGUUUGUCAAAGACAUGAUGGAGCUUGUCCAGCCCAGCAUCAGCGGGGUGGACCUUGAUAAGUUCCGCGAGAUUCUCCUGCGUCACUGCGACGUGAACAAGGAUGGAAAAAUUCAGAAGUCUGAGCUGGCUUUGUGUCUUGGGCUGAAAAUCAACCCAUAAUCCCAGACUGCUUUGCCUUUUGCUCUUACUAUGUUUCUGUGAUCUUGCUGGUAGAAUUGUAUCUGUGCAUUGAUGUUGGGAACACAGUGGGCAAACUCACAAAUGGUGUGCUAUUCUUGGGCAAGAACAGGGACGCUAGGGCCUUCCUUCCACCGGCGUGAUCUAUCCCUGUCUCACUGAAAGCCCCUGUGUAGUGUCUGUGUUGUUUUCCCUUGACCCUGGGCUUUCCUAUCCUCCCAAAGACUCAGCUCCCCUGUUAGAUGGCUCUGCCUGUCCUUCCCCAGUCACCAGGGUGGGGGGGACAGGGGCAGCUGAGUGCAUUCAUUUUGUGCUUUUCUUGUGGGCUUUCUGCUUAGUCUGAAAGGUGUGUGGCAUUCAUGGCAAUCCUGUAACUUCAACAUAGAUUUUUUUGUGUGUGUGGAAAUAAAUCUGCAAUUGGAAACAAAAA